AGAGCAGCCUUGGCGCUACGGAGGAGCCUAGGGCUAACCCUCAGCCAUACCUGGGGCUGGUCCUGGAGUUGCUACGCAGGGUUGUGGCAGCACUGACUGAAGGUAUGAGACCCGAUUCUCAUCCUUAUGGUUUUCCAUGGGAAUUGGUGAUACGUGCAGCUGUUGCUGGAUUUUUUGCUGUUCUCUUCUUGUGGAGAAGUUUUAGAUCAGUUACGAGUCGGCUUUAUGUGAGAAGAGAGAAAAAGUUUGCUGUGGCACUUUCUGGACUAAUUGAAGAAAAAUGUAAACUACUUGAAAAAUUUAGCCUUGUUCAAAAAGAGUAUGAAGGCUAUGAAGUAGAGUCAUCUUUAAAGAAUGCCAGCUUUGAGAAGGAGGCAACAGAAGCACAAAGUUUGGAGGCAACCUGCGAAAAGCUGAACAGGUUCAAUUCUGAACUUGUGCAUGAAAUACUCUGUCUAGAAAAAGAGUUAAAAGAAGAGAAAUCUAAACAUUCUGAACAAAAUGAAUUGAUGGCGGAUAUUUCCAAAAGGAUACAGUCGCUAGAAGAUGAGUCAAAAUCCCUCAAAUCACAAGUAGCUGAAGCCAAAAUGACCUUCAAGAGAUUUCAAGCGAAUGAAGAACGGUUGGAGAUAGAAAUACAAGAUGCUUGGAAAGAAAAUUCUGAACUUCAGGAAAGCCAGAAACAGCUUUUGCAAGAAGCUGAAGUAUGGAAAGAACAAGUGAGUGAACUUAUUAAACAGAAAAGAACAUUUGAAGACUCCAAAGUACAUGCAGAACAAGUUCUAAAUGAUAAAGAAAAUCACAUCAAGACUCUGACUGAACGCUUGCUAAAGAUGAAAGAUGGGGUUGCUAUGCUUGAAGAAGAUGUAACGGAUGAUGAUAACUUGGAAUUAGAAAUGAACAGUGAAUCGGAAGAUGGUGCUUACUUAGAUAAUCCUCCAAAAGGAGCUUUGAAGAAACUGAUUCAUGCUGCUAAGUUAAAUGCUUCCUUAAAAACCUUAGAAGGAGAAAGAAACCAAAUUUAUAUUCAAUUAUCUGAAGUUGAUAAAACAAAGGAAGAGCUUACAGAGCAUAUUAAAAAUCUUCAGACUGAACAAGCAUCUUUGCAGUCAGAAAACACACAUUUUGAAAGUGAGAAUCAGAAGCUUCAGCAGAAACUUAAAGUAAUGACUGAAUUAUAUCAAGAAAAUGAAAUGAAACUCUACAGGAAAUUAAUAGUAGAGGAAAAAUGCCGGUUAGAGAAAGAAGAGAAACUUUCUAAAGUAGACGAAAUGAUCAGCCAUGCCACUGAAGAGCUGGAGACCUACCGAAAGCGAGCCAAAGAUCUUAAAGAAUUUGAGAAAACUAUUCAUUUUUAUCAAAAGAAGAUUAUUCUCCAUGAGAAAAAAGCACAUGAUAAUUGGUCGGCAGCUUGGACUGCUGAAAGAAACCUCAAUGAUUUAAGGAAAGAAAAUGCUCACAACAGACAAAAAUUAACUGAAAUAGAGUUUAAAAUAAAACUUUUAGAAAAAGAUCCUUAUGGACUUGAUGUUCCAAAUACAGCAUUUGGCAGACAGCAUUCCCCAUAUGGUCCCUCACCAUUGGGUUGGCCUUCAUCUGAAACGAGAGCUUCUCUCUAUCCUCCAACUUUGUUGGAAGGUCCUCUCAGACUCUCACCUUUGCUUCCACGGGGAGGAGGAAGAGGCUCCAGAGGCCCAGGGAAUCCUCCGGACCAUCAGAUUACCAAAGAAAGAGGAGAAUCAAGCUGUGAUAGGUUAACUGAUCCUCACAGGGCUCCUUCUGACGCUGGGCCCCUGGCACCUCCGUGGGAACAGGACUAUAGGAUGAUGUUUCCUCCACCAGGACAAUCAUAUCCUGAUUCAGCUCUCCCUCCACAAAGGCAAGACAGAUUUUAUUCUAAUUGUGCUAGACUCUCUGGACCAGCAGAACUCAGAAGUUUUAAUAUGCCUUCUUUGGAUAAAAUGGAUGGGUCAAUGCCUUCAGAAAUGGAAUCCAGUAGAAAUGAUACCAAAGAUAAUCUUGGUAAUUUAAAGGUGCCUGAUUCAUCUCUCCCCGCUGAAAAUGAAGCAACUGGCCCUGGCUUUGUUCCUCCACCUCUUGCUCCAAUCAGAGGUUUAUUGUUUCCAGUAGAUACAAGGGGCCCGUUCAUAAGAAGAGGACCUCCUUUCCCCCCACCUCCUCCAGGAACCGUGUUUGGAGCUUCUCCAGAUUAUUUUUCUCCAAGGGAUGUCCCAGGUCCACCACGUGCUCCAUUUGCAAUGAGAAAUGUCUAUUUACCGAGAGGUUUUCUUCCUUACCGUCCCCCAAGACCUGCAUUUUUCCCCCCAGCCCCCACAUUCUGAAGGUAGAAUGAGUUUCCAUCAGGGUUGAGUCCGACUUCAAAUGAGCCUGCUGCUGAACAUCCAGAACGACAGCAAGAAACCUAACAACAUGUUUGCCCUCUUCAAAAGUAAUUUUGACUGAUCUCAUUUUCAGUUUAAGUAACUGCUGUUACUUAAGUGAUUACACUUUUGUUCAGAUUGAAACUUAAUGGAACUAUAAUUCCCAGGAUAGUAUUUUGUAAAUGAGGAUGAUUUAAAUAUGAAUCUUAUGAGUAAAUUAUUUCAUUUUAUUUUAUUCUAGAUAGUAUAACUUUUAAUUUGAUUAAUCCACUAUUAUAUAAAGAAUGGUGGGAGCUUUAUAUAUGUAAUCUUGCAGGUGGGGAGGCUUUAAAUUGUCUUUAUGUCAAGAACUGUAUUUACUGUGGUUGUAGACAAAUGUGAAAGUAACUUUAUGCUUAAAUAAGUUUUAGUUGAUUAAAAAAAUUUAAAAAAUUUAAAAAAAGAAAUAUAUAAAUAUGCACAGGUGGGAAGGUAGAAUACUAUGUAACUGUUAGAAUAUUUCACUUUAAACCAAGAUGAUCUUGGAUCUCCUGUCUUAUAGAUUUUAUAUCCUCUUUCAGUACUUUGAGAGUGUAAAACAUUUAUAGCAGAAAGUAUUCGUGUUUCCUCUGUUUUCCUCAAGAAUGGUUUCUUCGCCCUCCCUUUCCUUCCCUUCGUCUUCCCUAAGCUAAUUUCUUCCUAUGUUUGUCAUCAUAUCAUUACAUAAUUGUGUUGUUAUUUCUUUUGUUUUAUUUUUAUUUGGUGGGAACAACUUUAUCCAGAACUUUUACUUGCCCCAGAAUUAUAUAGAUCAGUUUCUCCUGACUUCUUUCCCAACCUUUACCUCUGUUGGUGUUCUAAUAGUUUUAGUUUUAUGUUCUGCUUUUCUCUUGCUGUGGCAAGGGGAAGGAGUAAAUCUAAGAUAGUGCUUAAUUGCAGUUGGUGAAUUUGAUCUCUGAUUGAGCUCUCUUCUCUGGAAUUCUGUUAAAAGAUGAAAUGUAUCGUGUUCCCUGAGAGACGCCCUCAAAUUUUGGAUUAGUCCUUCAUGCAAGCUGGGCCACCAAGCCAUUGCUUCUUUUGGGGACAACCUGCCCUCACUUUUAAAAAGCAUCCUAGCUCACAUGCCUCCCCUAGCAGUUAAUGCCACUCCAGUCUCUGCUUGAAUGUAAUAAAAUAAAAGAAAAGUAACUAUUUGAGACAUGAGGUGCCCUUAUUGUACACUGGGGCUUCCUAUACAUUUUCCGUCUUCCCUUGAACCACCACUAUCCUCAGCUACUUUAUGCUUCUGUUCUGUUAAAGCCCUAUUUGCUAGUGGAAAAAUUUAACUCCUGGUGAUUUUUUUAAUACUAGGCCUCUUGCCUUCCUUCCAGUGAGAGAAAAAUAGAAUGGUAAGCCUAGUGGUUUCUUCCUUCACUGUUGAAUACUAUUUAUCCAAGGUAUCAAGGAAGAACUUCUAAUCAGAAAAGACAUGUAUUAUUUUCACAACUGGGUAGCAUAUCUCACUCCCAGAAUGGAAGUUAGGUGGGAAUUGCAAGAUUAAGGAGAUUUUUCUGGAUUUCUGUCUAUGUAUCAUAUCCACAGAACUCUUUCUAGAGGAAUUUUAUAUUGAGCCAGGCAUCCAUUUCCACAGUCUUGCAUUUCUAGAUACUUCCAAAGUUAUAGCACUGUUCCUAAAUCAUUUUUGGCUUUAUUUAUUAAUUUAUUGUUCACUUCAUUUCAUUAGGUUCAGUAUGAAACAGGUAUUGUCAUCUCUUUGUGUCUACUUUGCCACCUUUCCCCAGAAUAGGCCUGAAUGAGAUUGAAAACGUUACUUCAGUUCCUUGUGUCUGACAUUGCUUGUUUGUAACUAAGAAAAAUAAUAUUUGCUUUUGUUGAAUGACUACUAAUUUUUUUCCAUGAACCUAAUAAACUAAAAAGAAAGUUGAAAUAAUAAAGAGUGAAUAAGUAUAAAAAUCCA